GUAGCGCUCUCGCCCUGGCCAUGGAGCGGCCGGCGCCCGGCGAGGUGGUCAUGAGCCAAGCCAUCCAGCCGGCGCACGCCACUGCGCGCGGCGAGCUGAGCGCGGGGCAGCUGCUCAAGUGGAUCGACACCACCGCCUGCCUGGCGGCUGAGAAACAUGCUGGAGUUUCCUGCGUUACAGCCUCAGUGGAUGACAUACAGUUUGAGGAGACAGCUAGAGUUGGACAAGUUAUAACCAUCAAAGCAAAAGUUACUAGAGCAUUCAGCACAAGCAUGGAGAUCAGUAUCAAGGUCAUGGUACAGGAUAUGCUCACUGGCAUUGAGAAGCUUGUUAGUGUGGCUUUCUCCACAUUUGUAGCCAAACCAGUUGGAAAAGAAAAGAUUCAUUUAAAACCAGUCACACUUCUAACUGAACAAGAUCAUGUGGAACAUAAUCUGGCUGCUGAGAGAAGGAAAGUUCGAUUACAACAUGAAGAUACCUUUAACAAUUUAAUGAAGGAAAGUAGCAAAUUUGAUGAUCUCAUUUUUGAUGAAGAGGAAGGAGCGGUUUCCACAAGGGGCACCUCCGUUCAGAGCAUUGAACUGGUCCUCCCACCCCAUGCAAACCAUCACGGAAAUACAUUUGGUGGCCAGAUUAUGGCGUGGAUGGAGACAGUGGCUACUAUUUCUGCAAGCCGCCUGUGUUGGGCUCAUCCCUUUCUGAAGUCCGUAGAUAUGUUUAAGUUCCGGGGACCAUCUACAGUUGGAGAUCGUCUUGUCUUCACUGCCAUUGUCAACAAUACAUUUCAGACCUGUGUUGAAGUUGGAGUUCGCGUGGAGGCCUUUGACUGUCAGGAAUGGGCCGAGGGCCGAGGGCGUCACAUCAACAGUGCUUUUCUCAUUUACAAUGCUGCUGAUGAUAAGGAAAAUCUCAUCACGUUUCCCAGAAUCCAACCCAUUUCAAAGGAUGAUUUCAGACGCUAUCGGGGAGCUAUUGCACGCAAGCGAAUUCGCCUAGGCAGAAAAUAUGUUAUUUCCCACAAAGAAGAGGUUCCACUUUGCAUACACUGGGAUAUCAGCAAGCAGGCAUCCCUGAGUGACAGCAAUGUGGAGGCCCUCAAAAAACUGGCAGCCAAAAGGGGUUGGGAGGUUACCAGCACUGUGGAAAAGAUAAAAAUAUAUACUCUGGAAGAGCAUGAUGUUUUAUCUGUUUGGGUUGAAAAGCACGUGGGAAGUCCAGCACAUUUGGCUUAUCGUCUCUUGUCUGACUUUACAAAGCGACCUUUGUGGGACCCCCAUUUUGUGUCCUGUGAAGUCAUAGACUGGGUGAGUGAAGAUGAUCAGCUGUAUCACAUCACCUGUCCUAUACUGAAUGAUGACAAACCCAAAGACUUGGUAGUACUCGUAUCACGAAGAAAACCCCUCAAAGAUGGUAACACUUACACAGUGGCAGUGAAGUCGGUCAUUUUGCCAUCGGUCCCCCCGUCUCCACAGUACAUCAGAAGUGAAAUCAUAUGUGCCGGAUUUCUCAUCCAUGCUAUUGACAGCAAUUCAUGCAUCGUAUCUUACUUUAACCAUAUGUCUGCUAGCAUCCUUCCUUACUUUGCUGGAAAUCUUGGUGGCUGGUCAAAAUCCAUUGAAGAAACAGCAGCCUCUUGUAUACAGUUCUUAGAGAAUCCUCCUGAUGAUGGAGCACUAAAUUGUACCCACCCACUGCUUCUUGCACCUGGCCUUGAGAAGUAGGAAAAAGAAAUGAGAUAUGAUGGAAGGCACUUGUUCAAGAGCUAUUGCACAGAAGCCUGGAUCUUAACAAUGCUUAGACAAUCAAGAGUCUGUGAACCCUUGGACCUGUAAACAAAAGAUGUAAGCAGAUGCACUUUCCUGAAUAGCAUGUCAGAUUCUCAAACAGUCAAUGGCCCAAAAACAGAUUAGAAACUACUGUUCUACUGUACAGAUCAGAUGGGGGUAAGCAUUUAUGAAAGAAAUAAAGUUAAUUUUUGUUUCAGUGCCUUCCACUGGCCAGGCACCCUAACCCUAUAAAAAUGCCCACCUGCCUACUUUAAACAACAUUCCAGGAUUGUGAAUUACAACACAUGUGGUUUCUAAAAUAAGUGUUUCACUUAAUGAUCAAACACUAUUGCUUAAUGGUCAAGCAUUAUCUUGAUCAUGCUCGAAAUGUUAAGUGACUUAGAAAAAUGACCUAAUCAGAUACAAAUCUGGCUGAAUUUUCUUUUUUUUUUCCCCCAAAUCUUGACUUUAUUUUUAACAUAAAAAUGCAAAUGUGGAAACCCACCCUACUUUUCCCCCAACAUAAUGCUUUACCUCUUAAAAAUAAAGUACUAAUUCUAUAUACAUCAAAUGUACCAUACAAAAAUGUAUCCAGUGUUUCUAUUGCUACUAAAGUGUUCUAAAUUAAAACAAAUCGCAGAAAGCCCCUUAUUGUAAACAAAAGAUUACAAGGUAUAAAAUCAAGGCACACACAGGCAAAUAUGGCCAAAUUUUCACAUCUAUGGGAUCUACUCUCCUUGCUGCAUUAAUUUUUUUUUUUUUUUUUUUUUUUACAGCUAGUCACUUUGGUUGACCAGUGAAAGCCAUUUUUGCUCACUAGUCAUGUUAUCUACCCAGUUUUAUAAGCUCAAAACUGAAAUGCACCUGAGCAUUUUCCAGGCCCUGGCCUCUUUAUAUGCCAUAGUGAAAGAGAAGCACUUGAAUAAUACAUUUUAAUCCUUAUAAAAAUUCUUUAGGCAAAUACCAUAAUUCAUCAACUCUAAGACACCACUGAUUAUAAGAUGUAUCAUUAUUGCACAUACCUCUCAGAAAGAAAAACAGCUGUCAAUUAUAUGGGACCCACCAACGGUAAGAUACAUUCUGAUUUCCAAGAGAUUAAAAUUGAAAAACUGUGCAUCUUAGAAUCAAUAAAAUAUAGUUUUAUCAUCUCCACUCUAUAGGUGAGGAAACGGAGAUCAGAGUUUGGUAGUUGGCCAAAGCCCCCCAGCUAGUGAGUGGCAGUGCUGGCGCUGUAACCCAAGUCUGACCAACUCCAAAAGCUAUGCUUUUUCACUGGACUUCUCCAGGAGGGAAACCCAGGACAUGACACAAGAAACGUCUAGAGCCUGAUGGCACCAGCCAUCACAUUAACAGAUAACAACCUCCGCCUUAAAGCUUUAGACCGCAUAGACUUUACUGUGUGAACCUUAAUUACCCGAGUUAAAGAGAAAAAAGCUACAUGAUCCCAUACCAGACAAAUAACUAAGAAAAAAAAUUCAGAAGCAAACAUUACUACAAUAUUGAAUCAUCUGUACCCACCCCUCCACCAAAAUGAUAUGCUGGCUGAGGCUGAAUAUAUAAUACGAUUUUAAAAACCUCAUAUUAGCUUGAGAUAUAAUCUCUCUGCUUCUGUUAUGUCUAAAAGUAGAAAUGUAUGACAUAGUCUCACAAAUGAUGAAGCAAGCACAGUUGGAAAUAUACACCUUAGUUUUUUCUGAUUUGUUUUAUUAACAUCUGAAGUCAAAUUGCACAAAAAGCCUAGUACAUAUGAUAGCACUUGAUAAAAAUAAUGUAAUUCUCAAGGUUUUGCAAUUUAUUCAAGAAUUUAUUCAAGAACUGUGAUUGAGUGUAAAUUAAAUCACAACUGCACGAUGACUCACCAUUUCUGCUAUAUGAGGGUAACAGUACUUACCAUCAGCAUAGAGUCCUUUGGGAUUAUCAGGACAAGAUCUAGACAGGUGCCCCAUUUCUCCACAAACAAAACAUUUUGCAAAAGGAAAUUCGCCUGUAAAAAUCAACAGUUCCUAUUCAGUUGACAAUACAUAUGGCAAGUCAUAAAAUUAACAUUAUUUUAAAAUACUCUGAAUAAAAAAUAUAUUUACAUAACUUAAAAUUUAAUCUCAUAUGAUUUCCAAAUACUAAGUGGCACACUCGUAACAAAUUGUGUUAAAAAAAUACCCAAGGUGCUAUUUAUUGGCUUUCCCCAUGAACAAAACAAAAAACUGAAAGAAACACAUACCAAGAGCCGGGUCUACUUUAGCCUUACACUUGGUUAUUUCGUGCUCUGUGGACCCACACCUGUAACAUAUCCCAGUGCCCAUGUCUUGAUUUUCAAGGGCGGC